AUUCCCACCCAGUCCAGAAAUUGAAAUACUAUCAGGGGGCAAGAGCCUUUCUCUCCAGCUACACACUCCAUCUCCCGGGAGCAAGGGGAAACUCCGAGAGGAGGGCAACAGAGCCAGCAUCUUGCCAGGGCCCCGGAGGAGGGGUUCCCCGCUACGCCUGUGCCGGAGGAGUUCCAGUCACCGAGCGAGGGGCGCAAGGGUGGGUGCAUCCUGCGCUGCGGCGGGCGCGCUACCCAGACGCUGGUGUGCAGAGCCACAUGAAGCCUGCUGGGGACUGGGGGCCAGGGAGCAGCAAGCCAGCUGGGACUGAGGCGGACGCUGUCUCAGGGAGACGCUGACUCGCAAAGACACUCCCUUCCUUGUGCCUGGGUAAAAAGUCUCCUCCUGGGGUCCCUGGCCAUCCUGAAUAUCCAGAAUGGUGUUUCUGAAGUUCUUCUGCAUGAGUUUCUUCUGCCACCUGUGUCAAGGCUACUUCGAUGGCCCCCUCUACCCAGAGAUGUCCAAUGGGACUCUGCACCACUACUUCGUGCCCGAUGGGGACUAUGAGGAGAACGAUGACCCCGAGAAGUGCCAGCUGCUCUUCAGGGUGAGUGACCACAGGCGCUGCUCCCAGGGGGAGGGGAGCCAGGUUGGCAGCCUGCUGAGCCUCACCCUGCGGGAGGAGUUCACCGUGCUGGGCCGCCAGGUGGAGGAUGCUGGGCGCGUGCUGGAGGGCAUCAGCAAAAGCAUCUCCUACGACCUAGACGGGGAAGAGAGCUAUGGCAAGUACCUGCGGCGGGAGUCCCACCAGAUCGGGGAUGCCUACUCCAACUCGGACAAAUCCCUCACUGAGCUGGAGAGCAAGUUCAAGCAGGGCCAGGAACAGGACAGCCGGCAGGAGAGCAGGCUCAACGAGGACUUUCUGGGAAUGCUGGUCCACACCAGGUCCCUGCUGAAGGAGACACUGGACAUCUCUGUGGGGCUCAGGGACAAAUACGAGCUGCUGGCCCUCACCAUUAGGAGCCAUGGGACCCGACUAGGUCGGCUGAAAAAUGAUUAUCUUAAAGUAUAGGUGGAAGGAUACAAAUGCUAGAAAGAGGGAAUCAAAUCAGCCCCGUUUUGGAGGGUGGGGGACAGAAGAUGGGGCUACAUUUCCCCCAUACCUACUAUUUUUUUAUAUCCCGAUUUGCACUUUGAGAAUACAUCUAAGGUCAUCUUUCAAAAGAGAAAAAUUGGACACUUGAGUGACUUUGUUUUUAGUUUUGUUUUUGUACAUUAUUUAUGUGAUUGUUAUGGAAUUGUCACCUGGAAAGAACAAUUUUAAGCAAUGUCAUUUCUAGAUGGGUUUCUAAUUCUGCAGAGACACCCGUUUCAGCCACAUCUAAAAGAGCACAGUUUAUGUGGUGCGGAAUUAAACUUCCCCAUCCUGCAGAUUAUGUGGAAAUACCCAAAGAUAAUAGUGCAUAGCUCCUUUCAGCCUCUAGCCUUCACUCCUGGGCUCCAAAAGCUAUCCCAGUUGCCUGUUUUUCAAAUGAGGUUCAAGGUGCUGCUUUGCAUGCCUGCCAACCCAUGGAAGUUGUUUCUUACUUCUUUUCUCUCUUAUUUAUUAACCAUGGUCUGAGAGUUGUUUUUGUUCUAUGUAACAGUAUUGCCACAAAACUAUAGGCAAAUCGUGUUUGCAGGGAGAUUUCUGAUGCCUCUGUGGGUGUGUGUAAGUUAAAGUGGCCACAUUUAAGAAGGCCAAGCUUUGUAGUGGUUGCACAGUCACACUGAUAUGCUGAUUUGCUCUUUCUCAUUGUAUGUCUAUGCUUUGUCAUCAGUGCUAUAGUAAAUUACAAAGAAAUAGGUAGAUUGUAUGAACAUACCCACAAAUGCCUAUGAUUUAGGUUACCAAUGUAUUCUUUCUCAUUUGGGGUUUUGCUUCUGUCUGUCUGUUUAUUGGAAACUUGUACUUCAAGUAGGGGGAAUCCUAAUUCUAAUAACUCCUUAGCUAAGUUUUAUUAUUCAGGCAAUAAACAUGUUUUCAUGUAAUACUGGCUUACUUUGUAAUUUACAUCUGUAACUUUCAUAUUUCUAAAAGGGGCCAAUGCAAAAGGAGAGAGAAGGACUGGAUUUAAGCCAGUUUACUUAGAGUAUAUGAUAAAGAAGGCAGAGGAAUAGCUACAUAUUUGGCAAUUCUCCUCUCUGUAGUCACCCUGACAUCCUCACAAGAAAACAAAUCUAGCCAUUGCCCAAACUUUAAAUUUGAUCUCUAUAGGUCUGCUUAAAGACUCAAAUUUUCUCCAGUUUCUCUCAUAAAUUCAAUUGCAAAAGUUUCUGACAAGGCUCAUACCCUGUACCCUUAUGCAGAGCAAGCAUUCCAUCCUAAGUUAUAAACUACAGUGAUGUUUAAUUUUGAAGCCAGGUCUACAUUAUUUAAUUAAUGGCUUCAAAAGGUGGAGAUGCACUUUAUUUAAUGUCUUUCCCUAGCUAAUUCUUACUCUCACCUUAAAUAUGCUUUCUUGUUGCAUAUAUGCACAGAUACACACACACACACACACGAAAAUAAAUAAAUGUUCAUAUUCUUCUGUUCAACAGACAUUUAUUUUCUCCUCUCCCUUGAAUAAGAAAAUAAGUUUUCCAUUCCUAUGAACUGUCUAAUAUCUUUCUAUUACAGAAGGGGAAACUGAGGCUGGGAAAGGCUAAAUGACUUAUCCUCCAUCAGUUAUAACAGCCCCUGGUCUUCUUAAAUUUAAACACGGGACUUCCCGAACUAAUUUUUUUAAGGAUACUGAAAAAUGAGAGAGAGUGGUCGAAUGCCUGAAAUUUUGCUUAACUUACUGUACUUAAAAUCAAUUAUAACUUCUUUUUGUUACUCAGGGCCCCACUUUUUGUUGCUUUCUAGACUUGUGUGUAGAAAGAAGAUUAAUGAUCACUUAAAGUAGUUUCCUUCUUUAUUCUGAAAAAAUGAGGAAAAAAUAACAACAGUGGCAAAUAAAAUCAUAUUUGGUACUAAAA